ACAACACCCCUUGGGUGCCCCAACGCGCCUAGCACCCUGUAAGUGCUCCCCAGCUGUGGAUACAGGUUUCUCUCAGGGCAGCCCGCAAGCAGUGCAGCCCCAGCCAGAAGAGCUGGAAGGCUGGGCGGCCAGGCCCGCUGUGUCCCCAGUUUUCCUGUUGGAGUCCAUCUGCUGUGCUCUCAGGAGAGAAGGCUGGGUCUCUGGGAGCUCACAUCCUGUAUGCCCUCCCUCCAUGCCAAGCAACUUUGGGGAGUCCUGGCAGUGGUGCCAGGCGUUGCUCUUACCUGUACCAUAACCAGGAGGCUGAUGGUUGCUCAGGCCUCCCUCAAACUAGCCAAUGAGAAGUGCACGGGUCCUGGUCGCCUAGGAAACCGCGUGACAACAAGAUGGCGGCGCUGCGGGACGGCUAGCGGCCCUGCGUGGGAGUUCCUGACAGCUGGAUUCUAGAAGUAGAACUAUGAGCUCACCUUUGGCCUCCCUUAGCAAGACCCGAAAAGUGCCCCUGCCCUCGGAGCCUAUGAAUCCUGGGAGGCGAGGAAUCCGCAUCUAUGGAGAUGUCCCUGCAUCCCAUGACUCGGAGCUGAUGGCCUUCAUGACGAGGAAGUUGUGGGACCUGGAGCAGCAGGUGAAGGCCCAGACUGAUGAGAUACUGUCCAAGGAUCAGAAGAUAGCGGCCCUAGAGGACCUGGUGCAGACCCUCCGGCCACACCCAGCCGAGGCAACCCUGCAGCGGCAGGAGGAACUGGAGACGAUGUGUGUGCAGCUGCAGCGGCAGGUCAGGGAGAUGGAGCGGUUCCUCAGUGACUAUGGCCUGCAGUGGGUGGGCGAGCCCAUGGACCAGGAGGACUCAGAGAGCAAGACAGUCUCAGAGCAUGGCGAGAGGGACUGGAUGACAGCCAAGAAGUUCUGGAAGCCAGGGGACUCAUUGGCGCCCCCUGAGGUGGACUUUGACAGGCUGCUGGCCAGCCUGCAGGAUCUUAGUGAGCUGGUGGUAGAGGGUGACACCCAAGUGACACCAGUGCCCGGCGGGGCACGGCUGCGUACCCUCGAGCCCAUCCCGCUGAAGCUCUACCGGAAUGGCAUCAUGAUGUUCGACGGGCCCUUCCAGCCCUUCUACGAUCCCUCCACACAGCGCUGCCUCCGAGACAUAUUGGAUGGCUUCUUUCCCUCAGAGCUCCAGCGACUGUACCCCAAUGGGGUCCCCUUUAAGGUGAGUGACUUGCGCAAUCAGGUCUACCUGGAGGAUGGACUGGACCCCUUCCCAGGCGAGGGCCGUGUGGUGGGCAGGCAGCUGAUGCACAAGGCCUUGGACAGGGUGGAGGAGCACCCAGGCUCCAGGAUGACUGCUGAGAAAUUUCUGAACAGGCUCCCCAAGUUUGUGAUCCGGCAAGGCGAGGUGAUUGACAUCCGGGGCCCCAUCAGGGACACCUUGCAGAACUGCUGCCCAUUGCCUGCCCGGAUCCAGGAGAUUGUGGUGGAGACGCCCACCUUGGCCGCUGAGCGAGAGAGGAGCCAGGAGUCACCCAACACGCCGGCACCCCCGCUCUCCAUGCUGCGCAUCAAGUCUGAGAAUGGGGAACAGGCCUUCCUACUGAUGAUGCAGCCUGACAACACCAUUGGGGACGUGCGAGCUCUGCUAGCGCAGGCCAGGGUCAUGGAUGCCUCUGCCUUUGAGAUCUUCAGCACAUUCCCGCCCACCCUCUACCAGGACGAUACACUCACGCUGCAGGCUGCAGGCCUUGUGCCCAAAGCAGCACUGCUGCUGCGGGCACGCCGAGCCCCGAAGUCCAGCCUGAAAUUCAGUCCUGGUCCCUGUCCCGGUCCCGGUCCCGGCCCCAGUCCCGGUCCCGGUCCCGGCCCCAGUCCCGGUCCCGGUCCCGGCCCCAGUCCCUGUCCUGGACCCAGUCCCAGCCCCCAAUAAAGCACCCGCCCCCUCAA